CUUAGGAACGGGUUGCUAAGCUGGUGUUUUUGCUCCAAGACAUGGCUGCAGCUUCCCAGGGAGGAGCCCAGGGGCAUCUCCAACACUCAGCCUUUCCCUCCGGACCCUUUUAAAAGAUUCAACAGCACCGUCUCUCUCCACUUCCAUCCUAGAAUGCAGAAUCUGCAAAGUGCCUUUUGUAAAGUUUCUUAAGCUAUAUUCUAAUGGAUAUGGGCUGACAUUAACAAGGACCCAUCCCAGCCAAAAUGAAUCCCAGGGAAGAAAAAGUAAAAAUAAUUACAGAGGAGUUCAUUGAAAAUGAUGAGGAUGCAGACAUGGGAAGACAGAAUAAGAACUCAAAGGUUCGAAGACAGCCAAGAAAGAAACAGCCACCAACUGCUGUCCCCAAGGAAAUGGUGUCCGAAAAAUCCCACCUUGGCAACCCCCAGGAGCCUGUGCAGGAGGAGCCCAAGACCCGCCUCCUGAGUAUGACAGUCCGGAGAGGCCCACGGAGCUUACCUCCAAUUCCUUCAACUUCCAGAACAGGCUUUGCAGAAUUUUCCAUGAGGGGACGCAUGAGGGAGAAAUUGCAAGCAGCGAGGUCCAAAGCAGAAAGUGCAUUGCUGCAGGAAAUCCCCACUCCUCGGCCCAGACGCUUACGAAGUCCCAGUAAGAAAGAAUUGGAGACUGAAUUUGGCACAGAGCCAGGGAAAGAGGUAGAAAGGACUCAACAAGAAGUUGACUCCCAAAGUUACUCAAGAGUCAAGUUCCAUGAUUCUGCACGAAAAAUCAAGCCUAAACCCCAGGUUCCACCUGGCUUCCCUUCUGCAGAAGAGGCCUAUAACUUCUUUACUUUCAACUUUGAUCCCGAACCAGAAGGAUCAGAGGAAAAACCAAAAGCAAGACAUAGAGCGGGAACUAAUCAAGAGGAGGAGGAAGGGGAAGAAGAAGAACCACCUGCACAAGGAGGAGGAAAGGAAAUGGAUGAGGAAGAACUGCUUAAUGGUGAUGAUGCCGAGGACUUCCUAUUGGGCUUAGAUCACGUGGCUGACGAUUUUGUAGCAGUCAGACCUGCAGAUUAUGAAAGCAUCCAUGAUCGGCUGCAGAUGGAAAGAGAAAUGCUCUUCAUACCCAGUAGGCAGACAGUCCCUACAUAUAAAAAGCUUCCUGAGAAUGUACAGCCCAGGUUCCUGGAAGAUGAAGGCCUUUACACCGGGGUAAGACCAGAGGUGGCACGCACCAAUCAGAACAUCAUGGAGAACAGAUUGCUGAUGCAGGACCCCGAAAGAAGAUGGUUUGGAGAUGACGGCAGGAUCCUAGCUCUGCCAAACCCCAUCAAGCCAUUUCCUUCAAGGCCGCCAGUACUAACACAGGAGCAGAGCAUUAAGGCAGAGCUUGAAACACUGUAUAAAAAGGCUGUAAAAUACGUUCACAGUAGUCAGCAUGUGAUCAGAUCUGGAGACCCUCCUGGAAAUUUCCAACUGGACAUUGAUAUUUCAGGGUUAAUCUUCACUCAUCAUCCCUGUUUUAGCCGAGAGCAUGUUUUGGCAGCCAAGCUGGCCCAGUUAUAUGACCAGUACCUUGCAAGACACCAGAGAAACAAGGCGAAAUUUCUUACUGAUAAGCUCCAAGCUUUAAGAAAUGCUGUUCAGACUGGCCUUGAUCCAGAAAAACCUCAUCAGUCUCUCGAUACCAUCCAAAAAACCAUCAAUGAGUAUAAAUCUGAAAUUCGACAAACAAGAAAAUUCCGUGAUGCUGAACAAGAAAAAGAUAGAACAUUGCUUAAGACUAUCAUAAAAGUUUGGAAAGAGAUGAAAUCCCUUCGAGAGUUCCAGAGAUUUACAAAUACUCCCUUGAAACUUGUUUUGAGAAAGGAAAAAGCUGACCAGAAAGCAGAUGAAGAAGCAUAUGAAGCAGAAAUUCAAGCUGAAAUAAGUGAACUGUUAGAAGAGCACACGGAGGAGUACGCACAGAAGAUGGAAGAAUACAGAACGUCGUUACAACAGUGGAAGGCCUGGAGGAAAGUGCAAAGGGCCAAGAAGAAGAAAAGGAAACAAGCAGCAGAAGAACAUCCCGGUGAUGAGAUUGCAGAGCCGUAUCCCGAGGAGGACCUUGUGAAGCCCAGCCCUCCAGAGCCCACUGAUCGGGCAGUGAUAGAGCAGGAGGUGAGGGAGAGAGCAGCCCAGAGCAGGAGGAGGCCUUGGGAGCCCACGCUGGUCCCGGAGCUAAGCCUGGCAGGAAGCGUAACACCCAAUGACCAGUGCCCCAGAGCGGAGGUCUCGAGAAGGGAGGAUGUAAAGAAGCGCUCAGUGUACUUAAAAGUGCUGUUCAACAACAAGGAGGUGUCCAGGACAGUCAGUCGGCCACUAGGAGCAGACUUCCGAGUUCACUUUGGGCAGAUUUUCAAUUUGCAAAUAGUCAACUGGCCGGAGAGUUUAACACUUCAGGUCUAUGAAACUGUCGGACACAGUAGUCCCACCUUGCUAGCAGAAGUGUUUCUGCCUAUUCCUGAGACUACUGUUGUCACUGGAAGGGCUCCUACUGAAGAAGUGGAGUUUAGCAGUAAUCAGCAUGUGACACUGGACCACGAGGGAGUUGGAAGUGGAGUGCCCUUCUCAUUUGAAGCUGAUGGCAGUAACCAGCUGACUCUGAUGACCUCAGGGAAAGUGUCUCAUAGUGUGGCAUGGGCCAUUGGAGAAAACGGGAUACCUUUAAUUCCUCCAUUGUCACAGCAGAACAUCGGAUUUCGGAGUGCUUUGAAGAAAGCAGAUGCCAUCUCAUCUAUUGGCACAUCAGGACUGACAGACAUGAAAAAAUUGGCCAAGUGGGCAGCAGAGUCCAAGCUCGACCCAAAUGACCCCAACAAUGCCCCUUUGAUGCAGCUUAUCUCGGUUGCUACCAGUGGUGAAUCCUAUGUCCCUGAUUUCUUUAGACUGGAGCAGCUGCAACAGGAGUUUAACUUUGUUUCAGAUCAAGAAUUAAAUAGAUCCAAACGAUUUAGGCUUCUUCAUCUUAGAAGCCAAGAGGUGCCAGAAUUCCGAAAUUAUAAGCAAGUUCCAGUCUAUGACCGAGAAAUUAUGGAAAAGGUAUUCCAGGACUAUGAGAAACGGUUACGAGACAGAAAUGUAAUAGAAACCAAGGAACACAUAGACACCCAUAGGGCCAUAGUAGCCAAGUACCUCCAGCAGGUUAGAGAAUCAGUGAUAAAUCGUUUCUUAAUUGCAAAACAAUAUUUUCUUCUUGCUGAUAUGAUAGUAGAAGAAGAAGUUCCCAAUAUCAGCAUUUUGGGCCUAAGCCUUUUCAAGCUGGCAGAACAAAAGCGACCACUGCGGCCAAGGAGAAAAGGUCGGAAGAAGGUGACAGCCCAAAACCUGUCUGAUGGAGACAUAAAGCUGCUGGUGAACAUUGUGCGAGCUUACGACAUUCCAGUGAGGAAGCCGGCAGUGAGCAAAUUCCAGCAGCCGUCGAGGUCUUCAAGGAUGUUCAGUGAAAAGCAUGCUGCUUCCCCAAGCACGUACAGCCCAACCCACAAUGCUGACUACCCCCUCGGCCAGGUUUUAGUACGUCCCUUUGUAGAAGUCUCUUUUCAACGAACAGUUUGCCAUACGACUACGGCUGAAGGACCAAACCCUAGCUGGAAUGAAGAACUAGAACUUCCAUUUAGGGCUCCUAAUGGAGAUUAUAGCACAGCCAGUCUGCAGUCAGUGAAAGAUGUUGUGUUCAUUAACAUUUUUGAUGAAGUACUGCAUGAUGUCUUAGAGGAUGACCGUGAAAGAGGAAGUGGAAUCCAUACUCGUAUUGAGAGACACUGGCUGGGAUGUGUGAAAAUGCCAUUUAGCACAAUAUAUUUCCAAGCAAGGAUUGAUGGAACAUUUAAAAUAGAUAUUCCCCCAGUUCUUCUGGGCUACAGUAAGGAGCGAAAUAUGAUUCUUGAGCGGGGUUUUGAUUCUGUCCGAAGCUUAAGUGAAGGCUCCUACAUUACCCUCUUUAUUACCAUUGAGCCCCAGCUGGUUCCUGGAGAGUCCAUUCGAGAAAAGUUUGAGUCUCAGGAAGAUGAGAAAUUACUUCAAGCAACUGAGAAGUUUCAAGCUGAAUGUGCCUUAAAGUUUCCAAAUCGUCAGUGCCUUACAACAGUAAUUGAUAUAAGCGGAAAAACUGUUUUUAUCACACGUUAUCUCAAACCUUUAAACCCUCCUCAGGAGCUCCUUAAUGUCUACCCCAAUAAUCUACAGGCAACUGCAGAACUGGUGGCUCGAUAUGUGUCCUUGAUUCCCUUCUUGCCUGACACUGUCUCAUUUGGUGGUAUCUGUGACCUCUGGAGCACAUCUGAUCAAUUUCUUGAUCUCCUGGCAGGGGAUGAAGAAGAACAUGCAGUACUAUUGUGUAAUUACUUUCUGUCUCUGGGUAAGAAGGCCUGGCUGUUGAUGGGCAAUGCUAUUCCUGAGGGUCCAACUGCCUAUGUGCUAACUUGGGAGCAAGGUCGUUAUUUAAUAUGGAAUCCCUGCAGUGGACAUUUUUAUGGACAAUUUGAUACAUUCUGUCCCUUGAAAAAUGUGGGCUGUUUAAUAGGUCCUGACAAUAUUUGGUUUAAUAUUCAACGAUAUGAAUCUCCACUAAGGAUAAAUUUUGAUGUCACCAGGCCCAAGCUAUGGAAAUCUUUCUUUUCAAGAAGCCUUCCAUAUCCUGGCCUUUCCAGUGUUCAGCCUGAAGAGCUAAUUUACCAGCGCUCAGACAAAGCAGCUGCAGCUGAGCUACAAGACAGGAUUGAAAAAAUACUAAAAGAAAAAAUCAUGGACUGGAGGCCACGCCAUCUGACUCGGUGGAAUAGGUAUUGUACCUCUACUCUGCGUCACUUCUUGCCUCUGUUAGAAAAAAGUCAAGGAGAAGAUGUAGAAGAUGACCACAGAGCAGAACUGCUAAAACAGCUGGGAGACUACAGGUUCUCUGGAUUUCCUCUUCACAUGCCUUAUUCUGAAGUGAAGCCUUUAAUUGACGCUGUGUAUAGUACUGGAGUACAUAAUAUUGAUGUUCCUAAUGUUGAAUUUGCUUUAGCUGUAUACAUACACCCAUACCCCAAAAAUGUUUUGUCUGUUUGGAUCUAUGUUGCCUCUCUUAUACGCAACAGGUAAUUUUUUUCACUGUACUUUCUGUAUCAUGUAAAAACUACACUUAGGAUAUGAGAAAAUUUUAAAUUAUAUGCAUCACAUCAGAAGAACAUAUUAUUGGCAAAUAAUAAAAUUAUCAACUGUUUUCAAACUGUG